ACUUCCGGAAGCGGCGGCGCUCGGGAGGAAGUGCCGAUCGGCUGCUGGGGCGAAAAGGGGGCGCCGGGCCGCUCUAGCCGGUGAGGCCGGCGGGCUCUCUGUGGCUGCGGCUGGGAAACCGCGCGGAGGAGGUGCCCGGCCGGGGACCAGCCCUGGUCCAGCGCCUCCCUCUCUCAGCAUGGACGAGGAGAGCCUGGAGUCGGCCUUGCAGACCUACCGUGCGCAGCUGCAGCAGGUGGAGCUGGCCUUGGGCGCCGGCCUGGAUUCGUCUGAGCAGGCUGACCUGCGCCAGCUGCAGGGGGACCUGAAGGAGCUCAUCGAGCUCACCGAGGCCAGCCUGGUGUCUGUCAGGAAGAGCAGCUUGUUGGCCGCGCUGGACGAAGAGCGCCCGGGCCGCCAGGAAGAUGCUGAGUACCAGGCUUUCCGGGAGGCCAUCACUGAGGCGGUGGAGGCACCAGCAGCGGCCCGUGGGUCCGGAUCAGAGACCGUUCCUAAAGCAGAGGCGGGGCCAGAAUCUGCGGCAGGUGGGCAGGAGGAGGAAGAGGGAGAGGACGAGGAAGAGCUGAGUGGGACAAAGGUGAGCGCGCCCUACUACAGCUCCUGGGGCACUCUGGAGUAUCACAACGCCAUGGUGGUGGGAACGGAAGAGGCGGAGGAUGGCUCGGCGGGUGUCCGUGUGCUUUACCUGUACCCCACUCACAAGUCUCUGAAGCCGUGCCCGUUCUUCCUGGAGGGAAAGUGCCGCUUUAAGGAGAACUGCAGGUUCUCCCAUGGGCAGGUGGUCUCUCUGGAUGAGCUGCGCCCCUUCCAGGACCCAGACCUGAGCUCCCUGCAGGCCGGCUCUGCGUGUCUGGCCAAGCACCAGGAUGGCCUCUGGCACGCAGCACGCAUCACCGAUGUGGACAACGGCUACUACACAGUCAAGUUUGACUCGCUGCUGCUGAGGGAGGCCGUGGUGGAGGGGGACGGCAUCCUGCCCCCACUGCGCACAGAGGCCACAGAGUCCGACUCAGACAGCGACGGUACGGGUGACUCCAGCUAUGCCAGAGUGGUGGGGUCGGACGCCGUGGACUCUGCACAGUCCUCUGCCCUCUGUCCGUCUCUUGCAGUGGUGGGGUCAGAUGCUGUGGACUCUGGGACCUGCAGCUCUGCCUUUGCUGGCUGGGAGGUGCACACGCGAGGUAUAGGCUCCAGACUCCUCACCAAGAUGGGCUAUGAGUUUGGCAAGGGUUUGGGCCGACACGCGGAAGGCCGGGUGGAGCCCAUCCAUGCUGUGGUGUUGCCUCGAGGGAAGUCGCUGGACCAGUGUGUGGAGACCCUGCAGAAGCAGACCAGGGUUGGCAAGGCUGGCACCAACAAGCCCCCCAGGUGCCGGGGAAGAGGGGCCAGGCCUGGGGGCCGCCCAGCUCCUCGGAAUGUGUUUGACUUCCUCAAUGAAAAGCUGCAAGGUCAGGCUCCUGGGGCCCUAGAAGCCGGGGCGGCCCCAGCGGGGAGGAGGAGCAAGGACAUGUACCAUGCCAGCAAGAGUGCCAAGCGGGCCCUGAGCCUGCGGCUCUUCCAGACUGAGGAGAAGAUCGAGCGAACCCAGCGGGACAUCAGGAGCAUCCAGGAGGCUCUCGCCCGCAACGCUGGCCGGCAUAGCGUGGCGUCAGCCCAGCUGCAGGAGAAGCUGGCAGGAGCCCAGCGCCAGCUGGGGCAGCUCCGGGCUCAGGAAGCCGGCCUGCAGCAGGAGCAGAGGAAGGCAGACACCCACAAGAAGAUGACUGAGUUCUAGAGACCCCACAAGCACUAUGGACGAAGCGUGGGACCCCAGCACGGGCUGCCCUCAGGAAGACCAGUGUUGCCCGAGGAGGGGCCGGCCUGCUGGCCUGGGGCGUGCAGACACUGCUGAGUGGAGACAGAGCUGCGGGGUCCCAUCUGGACACUUACUUGCCCACCUGCCAGUGUCUUGGGCAUUUCCUUGGCAAGGACAUUAAAGUGAUUUCAUCACAGUGUCA